GCUUCCGGGUCACGCCUUGACAGCGGCUUUCAACCCCCACCUCAGCCCAGCAAUUCGUACCGGACCUACCGGGAUUGCUGCGAUCUGUUUAGAGCCCGUGCAGAAAGUGACACCGCACGUCCUUGCGUUUCGUGCCCUUGCCCCCCGCCCCCUAGCCUCAGCGAGACAGCUGCCGCGGGCCCUCCCGCAGCAGGCAGUUUGGAGCAUGUGAACACCUUGAGCCUUGAUGAGUUCCAGUAUGUGGUAUAUUAUGCAGAGCAUUCAGAGCAAAUACUCUCUCUCCGAGCGCUUAAUCCGAACAAUUGCUGCCAUCCGUUCCUUCCCACAUGAUAAUGUAGAGGACCUCAUCAGAGGGGGAGCAGAUGUGAACUGCACUCAUGGCACACUGAAGCCCUUGCACUGUGCCUGUAUGGUGUCAGAUGCUGACUGUGUGGAGUUACUUCUGGAAAAAGGAGCCGAGGUGAAUGCCCUGGAUGGGUAUAACCGAACAGCCCUCCACUAUGCAGCAGAGAAAGAUGAGGCUUGUGUGGAGGUCCUAUUGGAGUAUGGUGCAAACCCCAAUGCUUUGGAUGGCAACAGAGAUACCCCACUUCACUGGGCAGCCUUUAAGAACAAUGCUGAGUGUGUGCGGGCUCUCCUAGAGAGCGGGGCCUCUGUCAAUGCCCUGGAUUACAACAAUGAUACACCGCUCAGCUGGGCUGCCAUGAAGGGAAAUCUUGAGAGUGUCAGCAUCCUUCUGGAUUAUGGCGCAGAGGUCAGAGUCAUCAACCUAAUAGGCCAGACACCCAUCUCCCGCCUGGUGGCUCUGCUAGUCAGGGGACUUGGAACAGAGAAAGAGGACUCUUGCUUUGAGCUCCUCCACAGAGCUGUUGGACACUUUGAAUUGAGGAAAAAUGGCACCAUGCCACGAGAGGUGGCCAGAGACCCGCAGCUAUGUGAAAAACUGACUGUUCUGUGCUCAGCUCCAGGAACUCUAAAAACACUCGCUCGCUAUGCCGUGCGCCGUAGCCUGGGACUCCAGUAUCUCCCCGAUGCAGUGAAGGGCCUUCCACUGCCAGCUUCUUUGAAGGAAUACCUGUUACUUUUAGAAUAGCCGGAGAAGAUGUUUGCACCAUCGUGCAGGCAGCUCUGGGUGAGGUUGUCCCUGCAGUACUCCUUGUCACAGAAAACAGAAAAACAGUUGUUCCUGUUGUGUGGUUUAUAGAUUUCGAAGCAACAUGUCACAACAAUAACCUCCAUAGCACCUCCCCUUCCCAAACCAAACAACCCAACAAAAAAAAUCCCUCACUUUUGUUUUCUGUUUAUUGCUUACCUGGCUUUUUAUAUUGCAUUUUGCAAAAGAAGAGGUCUCCCUCAAUCCUCCCCUUUAGGGAAGGAGUCAACAGUGUAACUAAAUUUCUCUAGGAAGAUGGAAAGUACUUAAAUAAUGUGUGUGUGGUUUUCCUUUGGGGACGUGGUUAACGGUCCAGAAGAAUCCCUUCUAGAAAGCAUUUUAGGCCAGCCAUGGUGGCUCACGUCUGUAAUCCCAGGACUUUGGGAGGCUGAGGCAGGUGGAUCACCUGAGGUCAGGAGUUCGAGCCCAGCCUGACCAAUAUGAUGAAACCCCGUCUCUACUAAAAAUACAAAAAUUAGCUGGGCAUGGUGGCAUGCGCCUGUAAUCCCAGCUACUCAGGAGGCUGAGACAGAAGAAUCGCUUGAACCUGUGAGGCAGAGGUUGCAGUGAGCCAAGAUCGCGCCAUUGCACUCCAGCCUGGACAACAAGAGCAAAACUGUCUCAAAAAAAAAAAAAAAAAAAAAAAACCAUUUUAAUUGAUCUGUGAAAAAACUUAAGAAAAUCACAAUUUCAGCUAACAGCAAUUGUGUCCCAAAGAUGAAGAUACUAUAACCUCAAAUGGUGCAGAUCCAGAACUGGGCUGGAUGACAUCCCUACUGUGCCAUGUCCUGGGGCAUUUGGAAGGGACUGGACCUCUUUCCCCUCAUCAAAGGAAACAGCAGUCUUUGCCUCUUUCUGUUGGUUGUGCCCAAGGGCUACAGUAGCUCUGAAAUAACAAGAGCUCUGUAAUAACAGUAAUAAAUAGCUCUGAAAUAACAGUCCUAAGAACUCCUAAAGUCCUGAGAACUUUUCUUGUAAUGCAGCUUUUUCUCUUCCUGAGAAACAGUGUGUUCUAAUGGGAUUCCCAGGCAGUUCCUACACCUACGGUGUGUGUUCCAGCAGGGAGGAGUUAUGGGCUGGGCUGCCUUUUCCCAUGGGUCUUCAUUCCCAAUGGAAAGUUCACUCUGCUUAGUUUGGAAUUAUUUUUCUUUCAGUUGUUCUGGAACCUUUGCUUUUUAUUGAUUUAUACAAUACAAUUGGUGGGAGGGUGGACUUGGGAUGGGAGUGGGAAAAGCAUGUAAGAGCUCCUUUUGUGAUGGUCCAUCUACCCAAAAGAGAUCUGCUUUAGUGAACGAUACUCUUUCAUUUUUCUAAAUUAGAUCAAGUUGUUAUUGAUUUUAGAUGACUUGUAUGCAAAUUUGAAAAACUUUUUUUUUUAAAGCUGAUUGGGAACUACAAACAAUGAAUGGAAUCUACUGACACAGCUAAUUGGAAAACAGAUGUCUUCUUCUGUCCUAUUGAUGCUGGUGUUUAAAAAACAUCACUUAAAAAAAAAGAAUAAAUAGUUCUAAAAGCAA